CUUCUGCACUCACAGCCGAAGGGAAAGCAGCAGGUUGGGGCUUCUUGUGGCCAACUUCAGAGCCUGUCACCAGGAAAGGUAAGCAUGGGAGGAAGGAAGAUGGCGACAGAUGAAGAAAAUGUCUAUGGUUUAGAAGAGAACGCUCAGUCCCGGCAGGAGUCCACGCGGAGGCUCAUCCUUGUUGGGAGAACAGGGGCCGGGAAGAGCGCCACUGGGAACAGCAUCCUGGGCCAGAGACGGUUCUUCUCCAGGCUGGGGGCCACGUCUGUGACCAGGGCCUGCACCACGGGCAGCCGCAGGUGGGACAAGUGCCACGUGGAAGUCGUGGACACUCCGGACAUUUUCAGCUCCCAAGUGUCCAAGACAGAUCCUGGCUGUGAGGAGAGAGGUCACUGCUACCUGCUCUCGGCCCCCGGACCCCACGCGCUGCUCCUGGUGACCCAGUUGGGUCGGUUCACCGCCCAGGACCAGCAGGCGGUGAGGCAGGUGAGGGACAUGUUCGGGGAGGACGUCCUAAAAUGGAUGGUCAUCGUCUUCACCAGGAAGGAGGACCUGGCCGGGGGCUCCCUGCACGAUUACGUGAGCAACACAGAGAACCGGGCCUUGCGCGAGCUGGUGGCCGAGUGCGGGGGCCGGGUCUGUGCCUUUGAUAACCGGGCCACCGGCCGGGAGCAGGAAGCCCAGGUGGAGCAGCUGCUGGGGAUGGUCGAGGGCUUGGUGCUGGAGCACAAGGGCGCCCAUUACUCCAACGAGGUGUAUGAGCUGGCGCAGGUGCUGCGCUGGGCAGGCCCUGAGGAGCGGCUCCGGCGGGUGGCGGAGCGCGUGGCAGCCAGGGUGCAGAGGAGGCCAUGGGGCGCCUGGCUGUCGGCCCGGCUGUGGAAGUGGCUGAAGUCCCCCAGGAGCUGGAGGCUGGGCCUGGCCCUGCUGCUGGGGGGCGCGCUCCUGUUCUGGGUGCUGCUCCACAGGCGGUGGUCGGAGGCCGUUGCGGAGGUCGGGCCUGACUGACAGCGCAGGUCCUAAAACUGAAGGCAACUUGGUUAAGGGAGGCUGAAUUCUUGGAGCUGAAGGGAAAACUUCAUUCCAACGGAAGGAAUCCUGUAGUUUCAGGCAUAGUUUUAAUGACACAGAAAACUUUGCUGCAUCACCUUUGCAACUUUGCCAAAGCUCAGAGUUCACUUUUUAAGUUUUUAACUCAUUUUAAAUGAUGUGUAUGCAGAGUUUUAAAAUAAAUUCGUCUAACAAUAACUUCCUUUGGUAGUUUUGGUAGUCUAAUGUCAAGUAGCUUGUAGUGGGGACAAACGCAUGGCACAGGGAAAACAAGUGCCAUUAUUUUCGAGCUUUUUAAAAAAUUUAGACUGCCCCUCCUUGAUAAUUUUCUAGUUCUUAUACAUGGGUAGAUAGGUUCCUUUGUGAUCCUUGUAGACUUUUAGCAUCAAUAAAAGAAAUGUGGGGGUUACACACGUGAAUGUUACUUCUGAGACAUCAGUUUAUAGUACAAUGAUUUACUACCAAAAAGAUGAAUGUAACUGUACUGUUACAAAGUGGAAAAUAACAGUUUCCACUUUUCUAGAACAUAUUAUGGUUCAUGGCAUUCCAAAAUGAAGUAAGGGCCGGGCGAGGUGGCUCACGCCUGUAAUCCCAACACUUUGGGAGGUCGAGGCAGGUGGAUCACCUGAGGUCAGGAGUUCGAGACCAGCCUGACCAACAUGGCGAAACCCCAUCUCUACUAAAAAUACAAAAAUUAGCCAGGCGUGAUAGCACUCGCCUGUAAUCCCAGCCAUUCAGGAGGCUGAGGCGGGAGAAUCACUUGAUGCAGUGAGCCGAGAUCGUGCCACUGCACUCCAGGCUGGGUGACAAAGCAAGAAUCUGUCUCAAAAAAAAAAAAAGAAAAGAAAAGAAAAAGAAAAAGAGUAGGAUAUUGGGAAAAUAACAUAUAAUAUCUUCUAUAUGGUUAUUCAUAUUUUUAUCACACACACACACACACACACACACACACACAGUCUGUAUCUCGAGCUCCUCUCUGGUUAUGGAGAAGAGGCAGAGCACCAGGUGCAUAGGCUGAGACUGCAGACACCUGAGCAUCCUAUGCUGUGAGGCGAAAGCAUCCGGUUUUUUCGGGAUGGGCCUGUCCAGGAAGGUUCUCGAAUGCCACGUGAUUAGAAAAUUUGCCGCUGACUGGUUGUGCGAAUCAAACAAUAGGAUUUCCUUAUUUCUAUUUCUGAGCAUAAUGAGAACCCUUUAAGGGAACUCAUUGUCUUUAAAUCAGCCAGCCUCUAGUGAGGUCAUGGAGACAUGGGAAGCAGGUAUUCACAUUAGCUCUAUUCAAGAGGAAGAGGAGGAGGGAGUGUGCGCAGGCGCCCUAGGGUCUUCCCCAGCACACGUUGGGAAGAAGGGGUCUGCAAGCAUGCGCACAAUUGCCAGCUCAGGCUAAGGACUGCAGGAGGUUCCAGGUGGGUUGCGGGCUUCGGGCAGGCUAUGGUGAGGGGUCCUGAGGGCCUUGGUGACCGCUGCAGGGAGUUGGACUUUUUGAAGCGUGGCUCAAGAAAAACCCAUGUUUAAUUCCUGCCUUUCGCUUCCUCAGCAGCCUUUCUGGGCCCAGGCAGGGGCCUCGAGCCAGGGAAGGAUCCUUUGAUGACCAGAGGGGACAGCAGGGAGGGCACAGCGUGGUCGUCCACGGUCACUUGCGCACGAGCCAGUGCUGCUGCUGGUGUUAGACAACAACUUUUAUCAAAGUGGUUUAAUGUACAGCAGCAACAAAGCUGCUUUGUGGAGCAGGGCUCCCAAUAGGCAGUGUGCCCAGAGUAGCAGCUCGGAAGCAGUACUGCAAUCACAUUUAUACCCACUUUCAACUAUAUGCAAAUUUAGGGGUGGAUUAUGCCAAAAUUUCUAGAAAAAAGGUCGUAACUUCCAGGUCGUGGGAUUGUUGCUAUGGAAAGGAGCCAAAACUUCCAGCUGUUGCCUUAGCAAUGGUAACCUGACGUGGCACUGGUGAGUGUGUUUUAUGGAGAGACUCUUUCACCUCUUCCCUUUCAGCUUGUCUUCAGUGUGGUCUGGAGCCCAAUCCCCACCUCCAGAGUCUAGUCCUGCCUCCUACCUCAGUAAUAAAAAGUAGUAGUAUAUGGUUAAUUGUCAAAUACAUUUGCAAAGUGUAAUCAAAGAUACAUUACCAAUCUGAAUCUCAAAAUGUGCUAUCAUCUUUGAAUUUGAAUAAUGUAUUAUUAAAGAAGUUACAGUUUUCCUUUACAUUCAAUAACAUUUCUUUAGUGGUUUUCUUUUUCAGAUACUUUGAUUAUGAUCUUUUUUUUUUCAUCUUUGUAUCCCCGUUAUACAACCCAGUGCCUGGCAUAGAAAGUGGGAUCAACAAAUGUUUGGAAAAUGAAUUGUAAAGUUGACUUUCCUGUACCUUUUUAAUAUUAGAUUUCUAGCUACCAGACUUUUGACCAUUUUCUAAAUUUUCUACCAUAGAUAACAGAAAAUUCUUUCGCGCAAGCAUGUCAUUGUAUUAAUGAUAUUCUCCUGCCCUAAGGAAAUUUACUUCCCUUCAAGCACAGGGUCCCCCAAAUUACUGUAUUUCCACCCCUUUCAGCUUAUUUUAUCCUUUUCUCCUGCUACAGAACAGUUGGCAUUCACCAUUCCCUUCGGUAAAGUCUUUUUUUAGGCUGUGGCUUAAAGGUUGCUUUUUCCCCCAUAGCUCAAGGUUAGGCCUUGUGACCUCACUUAUGUAAUUUGAGUGAUUUGAUAGCACAAAUCAAUUUUAUACUUAAAUUACAGCAUAAAACAGCACUGCCUCCUGUUGGAAAAACUUGCUUGCUAAUUUUAACCAGACACAGUAAAAAUACUGUCCAAUACCUCAAAAAUUGUGUAAAUAUAUAUCCAUUUCAAUUGUCCCCCUUCCUCUCCUCUCCUUUUAUCUCUUGGAAGAUAAAAAUGUAUGGGUCCUGUGCUGAUAAUGUUUCUGUUCAUAUUUCUAUGCCCUGGUACCUGGAUCAGCUUUUGUUCUACACAAAAAGACUUGUAUCUGGCUUAUUUCUGAAAGCUAGUGUUGGCCAUGAUGAACUUUUAGAGCAAAAGAUUUCAGGCAGAGUACAUUCUUACAUAUUCUUACACAAUCAAUAUUCAGUUCCAGCCCGCACAGUAGCCCUAGCAAAUGCCAGUGCUCCUUCCAGAGAUUCACCUAUGGAUUCAGUACCCCAGAAGAGAAUUUCUGUAAAUUCUUGGGGAAGCUAUAGCUAGACUAUGGCUCAACACUCAUUUUUCCCCCAUGAUUCUUAAUCUAACAGUGGCAAUGUUGGCCUCUUCUUAGGCAACUAGAUUCGGUUCUUGCUUAUUCUGCCAAUAAAAUACUUUAUUGAGAUGCUUACAAA